AGAGACGGGCAGAGAGAAGAGUAUAUAGGUGAUGAGAGCAGUGUUGGAGGGGAGGAUCGGCAAUAAUUGGAUGGCGUUGCAGCUGUUGCGCCUCUGCUGAACGCCCAGCCAGAGCGGAUUCACUUUUCACACAAAUCAACCGGAGGGAUUGUUGCUGCCUGCAAUCAAUAACUCAGCGGAGUGAGUUGCUCAAACUAGAGGCGUCCCUCGUCUGGGUCUUUGAGGGCCGUCCGGAUUGAGUCCCAGCGCUCUGCUUUCCAAACAAAGAAGUGGGCACCAAAACGCAGGACGAGAUUUUUAAUCCCCACUUCCACCACAACCCCGGGUGCCAAAGAAGAGUUGCAAACUGUGAAGUAACUUCUAUGAAGAGAUGAAGUAAAGAACGGAAGGCAAAUGAUUGUGGCAGUAAAGAAGUGUAUGUGCGCUCCAACCUCUCAGGGUGAAAACCGCGACUUCUGGGCGUGCAGGAAAAGCACGCUGGAAUCGAGUGCUGCAGACAUCCUGGACCGUGGUUUUUACGCGUGAGUAACGGAGGAGCGCACCGACCGGUGGAAGAGAGAAGUGGCUAACGCGUGUCCAAAAGGGGGAAAAGUCACAAGAGCAACUAUUAGGGUCGCGCUCCUAUUGGUCAGAGGAAAGAUCCCGACUUUAGAAGGACUUUCCUGCUGGCUGGCUCGCAGCGUCCCCGGAGAGCAAGCGAGCGCGCCGCAGCGGGAGACUAGGUUCUCUCCGAGCGUCCUCCGCAGAGGCGCCGCGAGAGGAGCAGGGAGCCGCAGCUCGCCGUGUUGUCUUCAUUUCGUGCAAUAAAGAAUUGUCAUUAGGUUUGCGUAUGGCAUGUGCUAUUACCCCACCGUAAAACUAAAAUUAGCAAAAUGUCAGGAAUGGAAAGAUUGAUUCACCAAGAUGCAAUUAUCAUUUAAAAGUGCUUGAUUGAGGUACUGAUGUUCAGUGAUUUAUUCUGCAUACCAUAUACAUAAUUAAAGUAGUGUAGUGGAGUAAUUUAUCAAUCUAGUUGAGACUGGAGGGGUGAGGAGGGAGCUGCUGUAUGUUUGUUUUAUUAAAAUGCUCCGAGGUCUAGUCCCGCCCCCCUUUUGCAAGAGUGAAACUGAUGAUUUCUCCAGCUCGCGAGGAAAGAGUCAACGGUUUGGGAUUGUGGGGGAGAGAGAGACGGAGAGAAAAAGGCAGCGCGAAGCAAAGGCAAGGACAAAAUUAAAUAAAGGGGGAAAAAAGGAGGCAAAAGACAUUUCAUCGGACGUGCUGCUUAGAACCCCAACCAUUCGUGCUCCGUCUUCCCUACCACCCCCGCCUCCCCUCCCAGUAUCCUUCAAUCCCCCCCGCCCCCACCACCCCCAGUCUUUUUUACGCGAUGUUUCAAACGCUGUGAGCUGUUCUCCUUUUCCCAUUCGUCUUCUGUCACUUCCUUCCUGGACGCAGUUUUCUGGACGAGUCUGGUUACUUUUAAUCCGACCGGCCGCUGAGAGCCACUUUCUCCUCCUCCUCCUCCUCCUCCUUCUCUUCCUCCUCCUUCUUCCUCCUCCUCCUCCUCUUCCGAGCGGCCUCGGCGCGCGCGAAUGCGCGGCCCCGCGCCCCCCCCCUCGCGCGCGCUCCCCUCGCGCGCGCGCACACACGCACACAUCGUCUCCAGCUCUCUGCUCGCUCUGCUCGCAGUCACAGACACUUGAGCACACGCGUACACCCAGACAUCUUCGGGCUGCUAUUGGAUUGACUUUGAAGGUUCUGUGUGGGUCGCCGUGGCUGCAUGUUUGAAUCAGGUGGAGAAGCACUUCAACGCUGGACGAAGUAAAGAUUAUUGUUGUUAUUUUUUUUUUCUCUCUCUCUCUCUCUUAAGAAAGGAAAAUAUCCCAAGGACUAAUCUGAUCGGGUCUUCCUUCAUGAACGAAUGCAGGAAUUUGGGAACUGAGCUGUGCAAGUGCUGAAGAAGGAGAUUUGUUUGGAGGAAACAGGAAAGAGAAAGAAAAGGAAGGAAAAAAUACAUAAUUUCAGGGACGAGAGAGAGAAGAAAAACGGGGACUAUGGGGAGAAAAAAGAUUCAGAUUACGAGGAUUAUGGAUGAACGUAACAGACAGGUGACAUUUACAAAGAGGAAAUUUGGGUUGAUGAAGAAGGCUUAUGAGCUGAGCGUGCUGUGUGACUGUGAGAUUGCGCUGAUCAUCUUCAACAGCACCAACAAGCUGUUCCAGUAUGCCAGCACCGACAUGGACAAAGUGCUUCUCAAGUACACGGAGUACAACGAGCCGCAUGAGAGCCGGACAAACUCAGACAUCGUGGAGACGUUGAGAAAGAAGGGCCUUAAUGGCUGUGACAGCCCAGACCCCGAUGCGGACGAUUCCGUAGGUCACAGCCCUGAGUCUGAGGACAAGUACAGGAAAAUUAACGAAGAUAUUGAUCUAAUGAUCAGCAGGCAAAGAUUGUGUGCAUUGAACAAGAAAGAAAACAAAGGCUGUGAAAGCCCCGAUCCCGACUCCUCUUAUGCACUCACCCCACGCACUGAAGAAAAAUACAAAAAAAUUAAUGAAGAAUUUGAUAAUAUGAUCAAGAGUCAUAAAAUUCCUGCUGUUCCACCUCCCAACUUCGAGAUGCCAGUCUCCAUCCCAGUGUCCAGCCACAACAGUUUGGUGUACAGCAACCCUGUCAGCUCACUGGGAAACCCCAACCUAUUGCCACUGGCUCACCCUUCUCUGCAGAGGAAUAGUAUGUCUCCUGGUGUAACACAUCGACCUCCAAGUGCAGGUAACACAGGUGGUCUGAUGGGUGGAGACCUCACGUCUGGUGCAGGCACCAGUGCAGGGAACGGGUAUGGCAAUCCCCGAAACUCACCAGGUCUGCUGGUCUCACCUGGUAACUUGAACAAGAAUAUGCAAGCAAAAUCUCCUCCCCCAAUGAAUUUAGGAAUGAAUAACCGUAAACCAGAUCUCCGAGUUCUUAUUCCACCAGGCAGCAAGAAUACGAUGCCAUCAGUGAAUCAAAGGAUAAAUAACUCCCAGUCGGCUCAGUCAUUGGCUACCCCAGUGGUUUCCGUAGCAACUCCUACUUUACCAGGACAAGGAAUGGGAGGAUAUCCAUCAGCCAUUUCAACAACAUAUGGUACCGAGUACUCUCUGAGUAGUGCAGACCUGUCAUCUCUGUCUGGGUUUAACACCGCCAGCGCUCUUCACCUUGGUUCAGUAACUGGCUGGCAACAGCAACACCUACAUAACAUGCCACCAUCUGCCCUCAGUCAGUUGGGAGCUUGCACUAGCACUCAUUUAUCUCAGAGUUCAAAUCUCUCCCUGCCUUCUACUCAAAGCCUCAACAUCAAGUCAGAACCUGUUUCUCCUCCUAGAGACCGUACCACCACCCCUUCGAGAUACCCACAACACACGCGCCACGAGGCGGGGAGAUCUCCUGUUGACAGCUUGAGCAGCUGUAGCAGUUCGUACGACGGGAGCGACCGAGAGGAUCACCGGAACGAAUUCCACUCCCCCAUUGGACUCACCAGACCUUCGCCGGACGAAAGGGAAAGUCCCUCAGUCAAGCGCAUGCGACUUUCUGAAGGAUGGGCAACAUGAUCAGAUUAUUACUUACUAGUUUUUUUUUUUUUCUUGCAGUGUGUGUGUGUGCUAUACCUUAAUGGGGAAGGGGGGUCGAUAUGCAUUAUAUGUGCCGUGUGUGGAAAAAAAAAAAGUCAGGUACUCUGUUUUGUAAAAGUACUUUUAAAUUGCCUCAGUGAUACAGUAUAAAGAUAAACAGAAAUGCUGAGAUAAGCUUAGCACUUGAGUUGUACAACAGAACACUUGUACAAAAUAGAUUUUAAGGCUAACUUCUUUUCACUGUUGUGCUCCUUUGCAAAAUGUAUGUUACAAUAGAUAGUGUCAUGUUGCAGGUUCAACGUUAUUUACAUGUAAAUAGACAAAAGGAAACAUUUGCCAAAAGCGGCAGAUCUUUACUGAAAGAGAGAGCAGCUGUUAUGCAACAUAUAGAAAAAUGUAUAGAUGCUUGGACAGACCCGGUAAUGGGUGGCCAUUGGUAAAUGUUAGGAACACACCAGGUCACCUGACAUCCCAAGAAUGCUCACAAACCUGCAGGCAUAUCAUUGGCGUAUGGCACUCAUUAAAAAGGAUCAGAGACCAUUAAAAGAGGACCAUACCUAUUAAAAAAAAAUGUGGAGUUGGAGGGCUAACAUAUUUAAUUAAAUAAAUAAAUAAAUCUGGGUCUGCAUCUCUUAUUAAAUAAAAAUAUAAAAAUAUGUACAUUACAUUUUGCUUAUUUUCAUAUAAAAGGUAAGACAGAGUUUGCAAAGCAUUUGUGGCUUUUUGUAGUUUACUUAAGCCAAAAUGUGUUUUUUUCCCCUUGAUAGCUUCGCUAAUAUUUUAAACAGUCCUGUAAAAAACCAAAAAGGACUUUUUGUAUAGAAAGCACUACCCUAAGCCAUGAAGAACUCCAUGCUUUGCUAACCAAGAUAACUGUUUUCUCUUUGUAGAAGUUUUGUUUUUGAAAUGUGUAUUUCUAAUUAUAUAAAAUAUUAAGAAUCUUUUAAAAAAAUCUGUGAAAUUAACAUGCUUGUGUAUAGCUUUCUAAUAUAUAUAAUAUUAUGGUAAUAGCAGAAGUUUUGUUAUCUUAAUAGCGGGAGGGGGGUAUAUUUGUGCAGUUGCACAUUUGAGUAACUAUUUUCUUUCUGUUUUCUUUUACUCUGCUUACAUUUUAUAAGUUUAAGGUCAGCUGUCAAAAGGAUAACCUGUGGGGUUAGAACAUAUCACAUUGCAACACCCUAAAUUGUUUUUAAUACAUUAGCAAUCUAUUGGGUCAACUGACAUCCAUUGUAUAUACUAGUUUCUUUCAUGCUAUUUUUAUUUUGUUUUUUGCAUUUUUAUCAAAUGCAGGGCCCCUUUCUGAUCUCACCAUUUCACCAUGCAUCUUGGAAUUCAGUAAGUGCAUAUCCUAACUUGCCCAUAUUCUAAAUCAUCUGGUUGGUUUUCAGCCUAGAAUUUGAUACGCUUUUUAGAAAUAUGCCCAGAAUAGAAAAGCUAUGUUGGGGCACAUGUCCUGCAAAUAUGGCCCUAGAAACAAGUGAUAUGGAAUUUACUUGGUGAAUAAGUUAUAAAUUCCCACAGAAGAAAAAUGUGAAAGACUGGGUGCUAGACAAGAAGGAAGCAGGUAAAGGGAUAGUUGCUUUGUCAUCCGUUUUUAAUUAUUUUAACUGACCCUUGACAAUCUUGUCAGCAAUAUAGGACUGUUGAACAAUCCCGGUGUGUCAGGACCCCCAAAUGUCACUUCUGCAUAAAGCAUGUAUGUCAUCUAUUUUUUCUUCAAUAAAGAGAUUUAAUAGCCAUUUCAAGAAAUCCCAUAAAGAACCUCUCUAUGUCCCUUUUUUUAAUUUAAAAAAAAUGACUCUUGUCUAAUAUUCGUCUAUAAGGGAUUAAUUUUCAGACCCUUUAAUAAGUGAGUGCCAUAAGAAAGUCAAUAUAUAUUGUUUAAAAGAUAUUUCAGUCUAGGAAAGAUUUUCCUUCUCUUGGAAUGUGAAGAUCUGUCGAUUCAUCUCCAAUCAUAUGCAUUGACAUACACAGCAAAGAAGAUAUAGGCAGUAAUAUCAACACUGCUAUAUCAUGUGUAGGACAUUUCUUAUCCAUUUUUUCUCUUUUACUUGCAUAGUUGCUAUGUGUUUCUCAUUGUAAAAGGCUGCCGCUGGGUGGCAGAAGCCAAGAGACCUUAUUAACUAGGCUAUAUUUUUCUUAACUUGAUCUGAAAUCCACAAUUAGACCACAAUGCACCUUUGGUUGUAUCCAUAAAGGAUGCUAGCCUGCCUUGUACUAAUGUUUUAUAUAUUAAAAAAAAAAAAUCUAUCAACCAUUUCAUAUAUAUCCCACUACUCAAGGUAUCCAUGGAACAUGAAAGAAUAACAUUUAUGCAGAGGAAAAACAAAAACAUCCCUGAAAAUAUACACACUCAUACACACACACGCACAGGGGAAUAAAAUAAGAAAAUCAUUUUCCUCACCAUAGACUUGAUCCCAUCCUUACAACCCAUCCUUCUAACUUGAUGUGUAUAAAAUAUGCAAACAUUUCACAAAUGUUCUUUGUCAUUUCAAAAUACUUUAGUAUAUCAAUAUCAGUAGAUACCAGUGGGUGGGAAAGGGUCAUUACAUGAAAAUAUGAAGAAAUAGCCAUAUUAGUUUUUUAACCUGCAAUUUGCCUCAGCAACAAAGAAAAAGUGAAUUUUUAAUGCUGAAGAUAAAGUAAGCUAAAGUACCAGCAGAAGCCUUGGCUAUUUAUAGCAGUUCUGACAAUAGUUUUAUAAGAACAUGAAGAGAACAGAAUCACUUGAAAAUGGAUGCCAGUCAUCUCUUGUUCCCACUACUGAAUUCUUAUAAAGUGGUGGCAAGAUAGGGAAGGGAUAAUCUGAGAAUUUUUAAAAGAUGAUUUAAUGAGAAGAAGCACAAUUUUGAUUUUGAUGAGUCACUUUCUGUAAACAAUCUUGGUCUAUCUUUACCCUUAUACCUUAUCUGUAAUUUACCAUUUAUUGUAUUUGCAAAGCUAGUAUGGUUUUUAAUCACAGUAAAUCCUUUGUAUUCCAGACUUUAGGGCAGAGCCCUGAGGGAGUAUUAUUUUACAUAACCCGUCCUAGAGUAACAUUUUAGGCAACAUUCUUCAUUGCAAGUAAAAGAUCCAUAAGUGGCAUUUUACACGGCUGCGAGUAUUGUUAUAUCUAAUCCUAUUUUAAAAGAUUUUUGGUAAUAUGAAGCUUGAAUACUGGUAACAGUGAUGCAAUAUACGCAAGCUGCACAACCUGUAUAUUGUAUGCAUUGCUGCGUGGAGGCUGUUUAUUUCAACCUUUUUAAAAAUUGUGUUUUUUAGUAAAAUGGCUUAUUUUUUCCCAAAGGUGGAAUUUAGCAUUUUGUAAUGAUGAAUAUAAAAAUACCUGUCAUCCCCAGAUCAUUUAAAAGUUAACUAAAGUGAGAAUGAAAAAACAAAAUUCCAAGACACUUUUUAAAAGAAUGUCUGCCCUCACACACUUUUAUGGAUUUGUUUUUCUUACAUACCCAUCUUUUAACUUAGAGAUAGCAUUUUUUGCCCUCUUUAUUUUGUUGUUUGUUUCUCCAGAGAGUAAACGCUUUGUAGUUCUUUCUUUAAAAAACAUUUUUUUUAAAGAAGAAGAAGCCACUUGAACCCUCAAUAAAGGCUGUUGCCUAAGCAUGGCAUACUUCAUCUGUUCUCAUUUGUGCCAUCUGCCGUGAUGUCGUCACUUUUAUGGCGUUAAUUUCCUGCCACUACAGAUCUUUUGAAGAUUGCUGGAAUACUGGUGUCUGUUAGAAUGCUUCAGACUACAGAUGUAAUUAAAGGCUUUUCUUAAUAUGUUUUAACCAAAGAUGUGGAGCAAUCCAAGCCACAUAUCUUCUACAUCAAAUUUUUCCAUUUUGGUUAUUUUCAUAAUCUGGUAUUGCAUUUUGCCUUCCCUGUUCAUACCUCAAAUUGAUUCAUACCUCAGUUUAAUUCAGAGAGGUCAGUUAAGUGACGGAUUCUGUUGUGGUUUGAAUGCAGUACCAGUGUUCUCUUCGAGCAAAGUAGACCUGGGUCACUGUAGGCAUAGGACUUGGAUUGCUUCAGAUGGUUUGCUGUAUCAUUUUUCUUCUUUUUCUUUUCCUGGGGACUUGUUUCCAUUAAAUGAGAGUAAUUAAAAUCGCUUGUAAAUGAGGGCAUACAAGCAUUUGCAACAAAUAUUCAAAUAGAGGCUCACAGCGGCAUAAGCUGGACUUUGUCGCCACUAGAUGACAAGAUGUUAUAACUAAGUUAAACCACAUCUGUGUAUCUCAAGGGACUUAAUUCAGCUGUCUGUAGUGAAUAAAAGUGGGAAAUUUUCAAAAGUUUCUCCUGCUGGAAAUAAGGUAUAAUUUGUAUUUUGCAGACAAUUCAGUAAAGUUACUGGCUUUCUUAGUGAUGCAGUGUCCGUGGUGCAUUUUUUUAAAUUAAUGUUUUGCUGUUUAAAUUUAUUCAAUUUUAUUGUGUUUUUUAAAAAGCAGCUUAUGCCACAAGCACAAAUGAGCUUUCUCAGUUUUCAACUCAAAAUAUUAUAUGAAAAGAUGGAUAUGUGUGUCUGUGUGGGAGGGGUGUGAAUUGGAUGACGGUUCUUAGGGUAUUACAGAAUUCAGCCAGUGGUGGAAGUCUAAGGUUCUUAUUGAAUGGUUCAACUUCUUUAUCAAAGAAGUUCCAUGAAGAUCUUUGAUAACCUGUUUAAAUGUACAGAAUUUUUCAAAAGCCACUGUGAAAAGCAGUACCAUAAGUUAUUUUUUAACUAAAAUCUGUAGAAAGUGUUUCCAAAAGAGUUCCUUUUUUCUUCUUCGAAGUAAUUUCUAAAAGUUGAAAACAUAGGCUUAUAAAUCUGAAUAAAUUAGUGAAUUCAUACAUUUUAGAGACUAUCAAAUAUAUCCAUUAUUAACAUUCAAUAAUAAUCUCUAAAGGGGAAUGUCCUUAAAAAGAUUGAUAGAAAGAUUAAUUUAAAAACUGAAAAGGAAAACAAGACACCACCAGUUAGCCAGCUGGAGAACUUGGACUUUUGCAUUAGUAGUGAUAUCUGCUCCAAAAAGAAUGCAGUUCGAGGAAAUGUUGCAUGUGGCUUCAAAAUAGCAGUGCUUUCUGCUUUGUUCUCUUGUAUUCAUUUUCAGCAAACAUGUAUUAAGCAAUUAUUAUAUGUAACUCAUGUGGUGAUUCCAGGAUGAAUGAAGUUGUAGCCCUUUCUCUUAGGAAACUUAUAAACUAAUAGGAGAUAAAAGGCAUUCUCAGGGAAGUCUACAAAGUGCUAUGAGGGAGCCACUUUGGCCAUCCUGGGGCAGAGCAGACCAGAGGCUCAGAGCAUGGACACUUCCUCAUCCACCCAGCAGAAGCCUUUCACUUGAUUUUGAAGGUGGGCAGGAUUGAGAAAGGCCCAGAAGGGGAUGAGUUCAAAGCUGUUUGUGGGCAUGUGACCCCUGCAGUCACAUAUGGCCCUAGCUUGUGUUUCGUUUAGUGUUCUGCUAUCAUUAUCCUGAUAAUAUCCUGAUAAUAAAAUUAUCCUUAAUAAUUUUA